AGCAGCUGCGGGAGACGGAAGUGGCAAGAGCGCGGCCUCAGAGGGUCGGGCGGACGCCGCCUGGGUGAGUCACCGUGCCCCCUGCACUGCAAGCCUGGGAACCGCAACGACCGCGUCUUGCCCGGCUCCGCCCUGGCCCCCACCGGCUUUCCUGAGUCCCGCCUUCUGUCAUUUGGGGCUCCGCCUCCCAGUCUUUAGGCUCCGCCCCUAGAACCUGGGCACCUGGGCUCCCCUGCCAACCUGGCCCGCCCCCUGGGACCAGAUCCCCUAGGUCUGAAAACCCUGGGCCUCCCAGGCCUGAUCCUUGUCCCUCCUUCCCUCCCUUCCUUCCCUGGGGCUGCUGCCAGUGGGCGGUGAGGCAGCACCUCUGGCUUGCCUCUUGCCGGUUCCCCCAUGAGGGAGAAUGGCCUAGGGAAGAGGAUACUGUGAACAGGGAGGUGGGCAGUACCACAGAUGGAGGCUUUUAUCCCCGCAGCCUCCCGCAGGGCUCUGCUGCACUGCCUGAGGAAAGCAGGCAUGAAGGAAAGUGUCAGUGAAACCUAGGCCUGGCUCCCUAAGUGAGCCUAGGAGGCCCUAUCCUGAAAUCCCUGUUACUUGGGCUCAUUGGACAGAUGCUGACUCCAAGGCCUGGAUUGGCCUGAUUCUGUCCCUGUUGUGUGGCCUCCUCUCCAUAACCUCCACCCCACUUGGUGUCAAAUACACUCAGGAGGACCUGUGCAGCCCUGCUGCCCUCUGAUCACAGGUUGUGGUCCCCUCCCUCUUGUCCCACUCUGGACUCUGCCCCCAGUAAACAGGUCAGGUGGGUACUACUCCCAGACUCAGAGACUGGCAAAACAUUCCUGUGGAUUCAUGCUCCUUCAACUACUGCCACUUCACCCCAAGAGUCAGGGCCUAAAAUGAGCCCCAGUUGGGCAGCCUGUGUCUCUUCAUAGUUGGCAGUUCUGCUCCCUGAGAAAGAAGUGUUCUCCCUCUGCGUCUGGAAAUCAGGACUCCUGAAUUCUGCUGAAUAAUCUUGGAUGACACUCAUUCCUGUUUCAGAACUUCGUGGCUGACUUCAUGCCCUGCAGGAUCACUUGUUGCUUUCUCCUCAUGUAGCUCCCAUUGCCUCUCUCUGGCAUGGUGACUUGUGGAGAGACUGGAGUCUCUGUGAGGGAGAAGAAUAAGAGUUGUAGAGAAGUGAGAAGCAGGCAGCCAGUACCCUUGCCACGGUAGAAUGGAGCGUGGAAUGACUAACCUGGCACCAUUCUAAGGGGAAAGAAAGGUUUAACGAAGUCACGGGAUUGAAGGACCCUGAUGGGCAGGGGCAUGGGUGAGGAGGGGCCCCCCAGCCUGGAGUACAUCCAAGCCAAGGAUCUGUUCCCCCCCAAGGAACUAGUGAAGGAGGAAGAGAAUCUUCAGGUCCCCUUCACAGUGCUGCAGGGUGAGGGAGUAGAGUUCCUGGGCCGGGCAGCCGAUGCCCUCAUUGCCAUCUCUAACUACCGGCUGCAUAUCAAAUUCAAGGACUCUGUCAUCAACGUCCCCCUCCGGAUGAUUGACAGUGUGGAGAGCCGUGAUAUGUUCCAGUUGCACAUUUCCUGCAAGGACUCCAAAGUGGUGAGGUGCCACUUCUCCACUUUUAAGCAGUGCCAAGAGUGGCUCUCACGGCUAAGCCGAGCCACAGCAAGACCUGCCAAGCCUGAAGACCUCUUUGCCUUUGCCUACCAUGCCUGGUGCCUGGGGCUGACCGAGGAGGACCAGCACACUCACCUAUGUCAGCCAGGUGAGCACAUACGUUGUCGACAGGAGGCGGAGCUUGCAAGGAUGGGCUUUGACCUGCAGAACGUCUGGAGAGUCUCACACAUCAACAGCAACUACAAAUUGUGCCCCAGUUACCCCCAGAAGCUGCUGGUUCCUGUGUGGAUCACUGACAAAGAGCUGGAGAACGUGGCUUCCUUCCGCUCCUGGAAGCGGAUUCCCGUGGUUGUGUAUAGACACUUGCGCAAUGGGGCUGCCAUCGCCCGCUGCAGCCAGCCAGAGAUCAGCUGGUGGGGCUGGCGCAAUGCUGAUGAUGAGUACCUGGUCACGUCCAUUGCUAAAGCCUGUGCCCUGGACCCGGGGACAAGGGCCACUGGGGGCUCCCUCAGCACCGGGAAUAAUGAUACCAGCGAGGCGUGUGAUGCUGACUUUGAUUCUUCUCUGACUGCGUGCUCUGGAGUGGAGAGCACAGCAGCUCCUCAAAAGCUGCUGAUCCUGGAUGCGCGAUCCUACACGGCAGCAGUGGCCAACCGGGCCAAGGGUGGAGGCUGUGAAUGUGAAGAGUACUAUCCCAACUGUGAGGUCGUGUUCAUGGGAAUGGCCAACAUCCAUGCCAUCCGGAACAGCUUUCAGUACCUCCGGGCUGUGUGUAGCCAGAUGCCGGAUCCUAGCAACUGGUUGUCGGCACUGGAGAGUACCAAAUGGCUGCAGCACUUGUCGGUGAUGCUAAAAGCAGCUGUGCUGGUGGCUAAUACAGUAGACCGGGAAGGCCGGCCUGUGCUGGUACACUGCUCAGAUGGCUGGGACCGCACACCGCAGAUCGUAGCCCUGGCCAAAAUAUUACUGGACCCAUAUUACAGGACGUUGGAGGGCUUCCAAGUGUUAGUGGAGUCUGACUGGCUGGAUUUUGGGCACAAGUUUGGAGAUCGCUGUGGCCACCAAGAGAAUGUGGAGGACCAAAACGAACAAUGCCCUGUGUUCCUCCAGUGGCUUGAUUCUGUUCAUCAGUUGCUUAAGCAGUUCCCCUGCCUGUUUGAAUUUAAUGAAGCAUUCCUGGUAAAACUGGUGCAACACACAUACUCCUGCCUCUACGGCACCUUCCUGGCCAACAACCCCUGUGAGCGAGAGAAGCGCAACAUCUACAAGCGGACCUGCUCUGUGUGGGCGCUCCUUCGAGCUGGCAAUAAAAACUUUCAUAACUUCCUCUACACACCCAGCUCAGACAUGGUCCUGCAUCCUGUUUGUCAUGUCCGGGCCCUGCACCUCUGGACAGCUGUUUAUCUGCCAGCAUCAUCUCCAUGCACACUUGGGGAAGAAAACAUGGAUCUUUACCUUUCCCCAGUGGCCCAGAGCCAGGAGUUCUCUGGCCGCUCUCUGGACAGAUUACCUAAAACCAGAUCCAUGGAUGAUCUUCUUUCUGCCUGUGACACAAGCAGCCCCCUGACUCGUACAUCCAGUGACCCUAACCUGAAUAACCACUGUCAGGAGGUCAGGGUAGGCCUGGAGCCCUGGCACAGCAAUCCUGAGGGAUCAGAGACAAGCUUUGUGGACUCUGGGGUAGGAGGGCCUCAGCAAACUGUAGGAGAAGUGGGUCUUCCUCCUCCUCUGCCCAGCAGCCAGAAAGACUACUUGAGCAAUAAACCUUUCAAGAGUCACAAAAGCUGUUCUCCAAGUUACAAACUGCUUAAUACCGCAGUGCCUCGGGAAAUGAAGAGCAACACCUCUGAUCCUGAGAUCAAAGUCCUAGAAGAGACUAAGGGACCAGCUCCAGACCCUUCUGCCCAGGAUGAGCUGGGUAGGACUUUAGAUGGCAUAGGGGAGCCACCUGAACAUUGUCCUGAAACAGAAGCUGUCAGUGCACUCUCCAAGGUCAUUUCUAACAAGUGUGAUGGAGUUUGUAAUUUUCCUGAGUCUUCCCAGAACUCUCCUACAGGUACGCCCCAACAGGCCCAGCCAGACUCCAUGCUAGGUGUGCCCUCCAAGUGUGUUCUUGAUCACAGCCUCAGCACCGUUUGCAACCCACCGAGUGCUGCCUGCCAAACUCCUCUAGACCCAAGCACUGACUUCCUCAACCAAGAUCCCUCAGGGUCUGUGGCAAGUAUCUCCCACCAGGAACAACUGAGUUCUGUGCCGGAUCUGACCCAUGGGGAGGAAGACAUUGGUAAAAGAGGAAAUAAUAGGAAUGGGCAGUUAUUGGAAAAUCCUCGCUUUGGGAAAAUGCCAUUGGAAUUGGUCCGGAAGCCAAUUUCUCAGAGCCAGAUCAGUGAGUUCUCUUUUCUAGGGUCCAACUGGGACAGCUUCCAAGGGAUGGUGACUUCAUUCCCAAGUGGGGAGGCCACCCCUCGGCGGCUGCUUUCCUAUGGCUGUUGUAGCAAGAGGCCAAACAGUAAGCAGAUGCGGGCCACAGGGCCCUGCUUUGGGGGCCAGUGGGCUCAGAGAGAAGGUGUGAAGUCACCUGUCUGUUCUAGUCAUUCCAAUGGACAUUGUACUGGCCCAGGAGGAAAGAACCAGAUGUGGUUGUCCAGUCAUCCAAAGCAAGUCUCUAGCACAAAGCCCGUUCCACUGAACUGCCCUUCUCCAGUGCCUCCUCUGUAUUUGGAUGAUGAUGGACUCCCCUUUCCCACGGAUGUGAUCCAGCAUAGGUUACGGCAAAUCGAAGCAGGGUACAAACAAGAGGUGGAGCAGCUACGUCGACAGGUGCGUGAGCUUCAGAUGAGGCUGGACAUCCGUCACUGCUGUGCCCCUCCAGCAGAGCCCCCCAUGGACUAUGAGGAUGAUUUUACAUGUUUGAAGGAGUCAGAUGGCAGUGAUACUGAGGAUUUUGGCUCUGAUCACAGUGAAGACUGCCUUUCAGAAGCAAGCUGGGAACCUGUUGAUAAGAAAGAGACUGAGGUGACUCGCUGGGUUCCAGACCAUAUGGCAUCACACUGCUAUAACUGUGACUGUGAAUUCUGGUUGGCCAAACGAAGACACCAUUGCAGAAAUUGUGGGAAUGUAUUUUGUGCUGGAUGCUGCCACCUGAAGCUGCCCAUUCCUGAUCAGCAACUCUAUGACCCAGUUCUCGUCUGUAACUCAUGUUACGAACACAUUCAAGUCUCUCGUGCCAGGGAACUCAUGAGCCAACAGCUGAAGAAACCCAUUGCUACAGCUUCCAGUUGAAUGCCGGGGAGAAACCUGUCCAAUUUUAGCAGGUUUGAAGGGAGGAUCUUCUUCAGUUGUAGUUUGGAAGGUUCCUUGGUGUGGCUCAUGAAAUCACAGAGCUCAGAGAUACCAUCUUGAGAAAUCCUCCUUGGUAUCAUGAAACUGGAGCAGAGGAAUUGCAAUUUAGCAGGAGGUCCUCUACUGGUGAUACCCUCACCUUGGGGUAAUGGUCCUAACCCAGACCCAGGGUCUGGAAGCUUAAUGUUGAGUUGGUGACUCCAGCCUCUUUCUCCUGGAGGUCACAAGAUGAUGAUUGCGUAGAUGUUGCCUGGUGCAAAGUGCCCCAAACAGCAAUAGAAAGGCAUAUGUAUAACCAAACUCCAAGUGAUAACCAGACCCAUCUCUCCUCCACCUUGACAAAAGCAGAUUAUAGUAUACAAGGUAGGAAUUCCUGUCCUAUUUGAGAUGAACUAUAUCCUGUACCUCUGUGCUCUGUGUCUGCAUGAAGGCUCAGCCUUUAGAGGCACUCCUUCUAGUUGCAUUAGUACUGUCUUUCUGUGGAGUUUGGUUUGAAGACUGGCUCAGCAAGUGGAGGUUUCAAUGUAUUUUUCAGUUGGCUCAUCAGCCAGCAUUGGUGAAUAUUCAGUUUAGGGGAACAGUUCUAGGGAGUGAGACAUUUUUGGGAGCAGAGGAAAACUCUGCUGAUGUUCGGUCCUGGCAAACAUUGAGUUAUUUUGAGCUGUGAAGGCAGUCGUCUCUGUUACACAGUGGCAGCUCUUGAGUUAUGCACUGUGAAGAAUGAGAAGGGAAAAGCAAAAAUUAUCCUUGUGAAAUAUCUGCUGAUUGUGCCCUACUCUUUGCACCUGACUUUUCCUAGUUGUCCUGGUGCUAACACAGGAGCUACACCUUGAUCCUCUCCUGGCAUGAAAAUAAAACAAAGGUUUUCGUUGUUGUUGUUCCAUUGCCCAUUUCCCCCAUGUUGUCUUUCCCUUGGCUGAUGCCUCCUCUGGGUCACAUUGCUUCUUAUCCUGAACACUUGACACCUUGAGGGUAGAAUUUAGCGUUUGGUUUUUACCUCCUAGCAUAUGCUGUUUGGUAUGUGAGGGUUUCAGUACAAAUGCUGCUGUCUAUUUCUGUGCACUUAACAAUGGAACCCAAACAGAAGAGAAUAAAGCCUUGAUACCAAAAUUGGGAAAGAACAUGUGUCCAUUUGGACCAAACGUUGUUGGUUUUUAAAAAAUUUUAUUUUGUUUUUUUGUUUUUGUUUUUGUUUUUUUUCAUCUUAAUAUGUACCAGUGGCACUUAACCAAAAGAUACAGUGAUAUAGCCAUGUACUGUGGGUGGGACAGAUACAGUCUCCUUGGCCUAUAAUGAAACCACUAGGACUUUAUACAGUUUUCCUUAAUUUGUUGACAUAUAAAUGGUAAAUUAUAUUUAGGCUUAUCCUGUUUUGAAAUGAUGGUAGUCAUCUUUCUUACUGCUACUUUCAUGUUGCUUUCUAGAAAACAGCAUUUCAUUCCAAAAUAACUAGGAUCUGCAUUUAGAACAAGAAUCAUUAUUUGUCCUGACCUUUUCAGUCCUACAGAGACGCAUCUGUGGUUCUUUUGUACUUGCCAUAGAUGUAACCUAAAAAGUUUUGGCAUAUUUAGGUCAGCCUAGCGGAACUUUUUUUUUCAUUUAAAUGGAGCUGAAUAAUGGAGAUUUUGUGUCUGCAAAAUUCCUGAGAUCAUUGAAAAAGUAACAAGCUGUUCCUUGUUUCUGAUACAUAAAAUUAUUUUAAGCAUUUUAUCAAUCAUUAAAAUUUACUGCCAGUUGUGAGUGGCUUUUUAAUUAACUUGUCUUUCAUUGCACUUCACUCUGCCUGUUUUCAAGGGGAGUAAGAUUGGUAACAUUUGGGGAGACUGUAUCUGUCUACUUAGCGUGGCUGUUUUGAGGGACUGUCCCAUCAGUGAACAAACUGCAUGGCCUUGGAGAGAGACUCUGGGCUCUUGGCUCAGAUGUGUUCAUCAAAUACUCCUUUCAGAGCUGUUGUGGGUGUAAGUGACAUGAUGUGGCCAAAAAUCCAAACUGUGCAGUUGCGUUGUGACAAACAUGCAAUGUGCUGUAAAAAUUCAAUACAGUUUAAAUAAAAUCUCUAUAUUAGU